ACUGCCCUCGCUUCCUGUGCGUCCUCAGGUCACCGCUUGCUCUAGUUCCCAGGCUUUGGCCUCCAGUGGACGAGAAUCGCGGAGCCUGCGGGGCUGGAGGUCUACCAGCCACAGUCUCUGCACGUUUCCAAGAGCAGCAGAAAAUGAACACAUUGCAGGGGCCAGUGUCAUUCAAAGAUGUGGCUGUGGAUUUCACCCAGGAGGAGUGGCAGCAGCUGGACCCUGAUGAGAAGAUAACUUACAGGGAUGUGAUGUUGGAGAACUAUAGCCAUCUAGUUUCUGUGGGAUAUGAUACCACCAAGCCAAACGUCAUCAUUAAGUUGGAGCAGGGAGAGGAGCCGUGGAUAAUGGGAGGUGAAUUUCCAUGUCAACAUAGUCCAGCCGCCCUGCCCGCAGGCCAUGUGGCCCCCGCUGUUGCUGCUGCUGCUGCUGCUCCCGGCCGCCCCGGUCCCCACCGCCAAAGCCGCUCCCCACCCGGAUGCUAACACCCAGGAAGGCCUUCAGAACCUGCUCCAAGGAGUCGGGGCUGGCGGAGACGGAGAGCUGCGGGCAGACUCACACCUGGCCCCGGGCUCUGGCUGUAUUGAUGGGGCUGUGGUGGCCACGCGACCAGAAAGCCGGGGAGGAAGACCUGCGGUUCCGUGAGAGGCGUCCAGGGCUGCAGGCCACGGCGACAGGCUCCGGGGAACAUGGGGCUUUCCCUGUCCACUCCCAAGGAGUGUGGGCCUCAACGCAUUGGCAGGGGACGGCCGUGUGCCCUCUCCAGACCCCACCCCCAGAUGCAUUUAUUAGAAAUAAUAAAGUUCUUUCUUAGCUA